UCCUGCCGUCACCUCCCAAAGUGCUGGGAUUAAAGGUGUGAGCCCCACGCCUGGCCAGAAACAGGCAUCUCAACUGAGAAGAGGCCCUGCAGCCUAGUGGUUAGGAUUAGGGACCCUGGAUACAGGUUUGCUUAGAUUUGGUACCAAAAUUGUAGCUCUGUUUCUCAAAAUGUGACCUUAGGGAGGUCAUCUACUCUUGUGCCUCAUUUUCUGUAUCUAUAAAAUAGGAGUAACAAUAACUCCUAUUUCCAUAGGGUUGUUCAAAUGAGUUAAAAGGUAUCAAGCACCUUAGAAGGCUGCCUGCACCUACUGUAUGAAUGCUUGUUGCUAUUAAAAGAAUAAUAUGAUUACUGAGAUUCUGGCAUUCCACAGUGCCUUCUAAUAAGUUUGGUUCCCAUUUUUGUGACCUGUUUUCUCUCUGCCCUUAGGACGUGGCUUUAUCUGCUCUUCUUUCUCAGCUAAUUGGGUGGCUCCCAGGUAUACAUCUCUAACCCACUGGACAUUGUCUUGUACUUGCUAGCCUCCUGUAUUGCCCUAGACUCUUGUUUGUGGCUAUUUCUUUGCCUAGACUUUGAAGUUGUAUGUGAUUCUUCAUCCUCAGUGCUCAUGUUUUUAAAGUUCUACUGUUUCUACUUGGGAGCUAUUUCUCAGUUUUGAACUCUUCUUAUUGACUUUACAUUCUGAGCUUGGUCACAUUAUGCUGUGAAUUUCUUGACUGCUUCCUAAUGUGAGAUCUUCAGAAUCCUCUCCCAUAGCAGAUGAUCCUCUUCAGCUGGUGUUCCCUCUUUCUCUGAACUCUGAAAUGAUUGAACUGCUCUCUCAUACAGCAAUGUCUUUUGGAAUUUAUACCCUGUGUAAGAAUGGUGUAAAGGUAAAUCACACCCACUGGCUUCCAGGGGCUCACUUCUGUCUGUUUUUCUUUAGUAACUCAAGGUCAGCUAAGGACGGAGGCCAGCUAGUUGCUGUCAGCCUGGCAAAUUAUUAUACCUGAUAGGAUGAUCUCCAGUCCAGGAUCUGACUUUCAGUUUGACAGGCCAGAGAUUUUAAUUUUUGUCCUUCUGGAUAACUCCAGAGCUGAACUCCUUGUCAAUCAAACUGACAAGAAUGCCAGUUUUCUAAUUCUGGUGGGAGAAACCAGAUAACUUGGAAACCAGUGGGCCACAAUACGAAUUGAAAAAGGAACCCCAAAGGAGUCGAUUCUUAAAAACUCUGCUUCUGUUGGUAUUAUCCAAAGAGAUGAGUCACCCAUGGAAAAAGGGCUCUCUGGUCUACGAGGAAGGGACUUUGAGCUGUCUGACGUGUUUUAUUUCUCCAAGAAGGGAUUGGAAGCCAUUGUAGAAGAUGAAGUGACCCAGAGGUUUUCCUCAGAGGAGCUAGUGUCAUGGAAUCUCCUCACAAGAACCAAUGUAAAUUUCCAGUACAUCAGUCUGCGGCUCACUAUGGUGUGGGUGCUGGGCGUCAUAGUGCGCUAUUGUGUCCUACUGCCUCUGAGGGUUACCUUGGCUUUCAUUGGGAUCAGUUUGCUGGUUAUAGGAACUACACUGGUUGGGCAGCUGCCAGACAGCAGCCUCAAAAACUGGCUGAGUGAACUGGUCCAUCUGACUUGCUGCCGGAUCUGUGUGCGAGCCCUCUCUGGUACCAUUCAUUAUCAUAACAAGCAGUACAGACCCCAGAAGGGAGGCAUUUGUGUUGCCAACCAUACUUCCCCCAUUGAUGUUUUAAUCUUGACAACGGAUGGAUGUUAUGCUAUGGUUGGCCAGGUUCAUGGCGGCUUGAUGGGAAUUAUUCAGAGAGCUAUGGUCAAGGCUUGUCCUCAUGUCUGGUUUGAACGCUCAGAAAUGAAGGAUCGACACCUGGUUACUAAGAGACUAAAAGAACAUAUUGCUGAUAAGAAGAAACUACCCAUACUAAUUUUUCCUGAAGGAACUUGCAUCAACAAUACUUCAGUCAUGAUGUUUAAAAAGGGGAGCUUUGAAAUUGGAGGAACCAUACAUCCAGUUGCAAUUAAGUAUAACCCUCAGUUCGGUGAUGCAUUUUGGAACAGUAGUAAAUACAACAUGGUGAGCUACCUGCUUCGAAUGAUGACCAGCUGGGCCAUCGUCUGUGACGUGUGGUACAUGCCCCCCAUGACCAGAGAGGAAGGAGAAGAUGCAGUCCAGUUUGCUAACAGGGUUAAGUCUGCUAUUGCUAUACAAGGAGGCCUGACUGAACUUCCCUGGGAUGGAGGACUAAAGAGAGCAAAGGUGAAGGACAUCUUUAAGGAAGAGCAGCAGAAAAAUUACAGCAAGAUGAUUGUGGGCAAUGGAUCUCUCAGCUAAGAGGACGGAUGACAGCCUUUAGAUCUAGAACUAGCCCUUAGAAAUGGAAUGGCUUUUUUUGUUUUGUUUUGUUUUAUUGUUUUGUUUUUAUUAUUGUUAAUCUUUUCUACAGAAUGAUUGUCUCUACCUCUUUAUGCCAGAGGCAGAACCUACAGGUGCCCUUUUUGGCUUUUGUUGUUGUUGUAACAUUAGCCCCAUGGAUUGUAAGGUGGUUUACUGAGUUAAAACAGAUUCUGCUUUUGUAAAAUGAUGGCAUCACUGUGGACUGAAUGAAAUAUUUGUAUAGAAAAAAGUGCUUGAAAAGUGUGUUUGGAACUCAUCGAUAGGGUAAUUCUCCAAAAAUGCCCAAACUCUUUUUCUGUAAUUAGCCUUGCCACUUUCUUCAGUCACUUAAAUGGUGAGAUUACACAUCAGUGCAAGAUGACCAUUAUGGUUAUGGUCUACUGCAAGGUUGAAAGGAAAAAUGGAGGAUUGUAUUUAGGAAAAGGGACAACUUUGUGGCCACCUGCUCUGAAAGUCAAAAGGAAAUGUAAAUUAGUGUCAUUAGUGUGUUGGAAGAGAAAUACUAUUCAGUAAGCUUCGCCAAAGAAAAGUGAGUCAAAGUUAAUGUGUGUGCGCAUUUAUAUGUAGGCAGCUCGUAGACCACAUUUUAACCAGCAACUGGUAACAAAGAGCUUAGUUUUCCUUGUUUGAAUGCUGUAGAUCUGUACCUAGUACCCCUCCCAUCUACUGAUUUGUUUGUUUUUGUAACCAAACACAUUUUCAGAUAGAAGGAGCCUUAAAAAAAAAAAAUCACAUUGAGUAACUUCAGUAUGAAUGAAUGAGAGUGUGUGGAGCUACCCCUCACCCUCCACCCCUUUGUGCUUUUUAUUCCCGAAUUUUCCCAGUCUCUUAAACAGAAAAAUGACUGAUAUAAUUAUCUUUUGGAAACUGAGCCUUAAUUUUUUUUAGAGGGGGAAAUAAGUUUUCCCCAACUCACACAGCAUAAGCAAUGUUUGACAGCAAUAUAAUGCCGUUGUAAACUACUGAGAGUAUUGUAUCUGUUCUGGUAACCAUGUACAGAAUGUGAAACUGUCUUAUGAAUAUAAAUAAAUUCUAUAUUUCUAAA